GGCAUGGGGACAAGUAAGCUGUUUUUUGUCAGCUGCCAUUGAUCUUCCUCCCUCUCCUCCUCCCUCCCUGCUUCCUUCCUUCUUUCCGAUUUAACCCUGGAAUCACGAGAGGCCACUUUAGAGACACAACCGCUUCAGAUGGGCAGUGAAAAAGACGAUGGAAAGGCCAGGACACCACGGAAGUUCUGAAGGGGUAGUGGGAACCGGUAGGAGCAUAUCAGUAGCUUUCCCUGCCCUUUUGUCUGCCACUGUGAUGUAAAUAUCAACUUGAUUUUACAUGGAGCUGAGGAACCUUUUAGAACCCAAUCGAAGAAGUUGGUGGUUCUACACCGAGCCAGGGGGAAAACUUUGUGGUCACAUGGGAAUUUAUACUUACUUGGUUUCUCUGCCUUUCUCACCAAUUUCUUUUUGGUUUCUUGAGAGCUGGUUGUGUGCAUAUGUGAAUACAUAUUGCAUGUUGAAAUUUUGGGUUUUCUUUUUUAAACCUUUAAUGUUCUACCCAUUUCAAAUGCAUUCAGGAUGUAUGAUGCUGUUUUUAUAUAAUGUAAACUAUUCUUACAAUGUCUUUUAUUUAAUUAAAAGAAUCAAAGAAACCAAAGUUAAGAAUUUAAAUUUUAUUUUGGCAUUUGUUACUGGUUGUGAUAUAUAAUUUUGGUAACAUUAGUGAGGGAUCAGGUUUAAAAAAUUUCUCCAAUGUUGUCUUCUGCAGAUUGCAAUUGUCUUGCAACUGCUGUUGGCAAACUAAAAAUGCUUUUGCUGGUUAAGGUAACCAGUCAUUUCCGAACUUUUUUUCAGUUGUAAGGGCAUAGAAUGAACGUGCACGCCUGAUUUAGUGUAUUAAAACUAAUAUCAUGUGAGGACAUUUUAUAGAUAAGAGGUUAGAAGGCAAACGACUCUAUUUUGAGAAAAAUUUGGAGGGAACCUUUCUUUCAAGAUAAAUAAAUUAUUUACUGUCCAGAAGUUUAUCAUGUAAUUAUCUGGAUUUUUUUUUUUCAUUUCUCUGAGCUUUAGCUCAGCCUCGAUGGACUCUGAUUUCAUAAAUACAUUACAUUUUUCAAUUUUAGAAGUCAUGGGAAGAGGCACACAACUUUGGGAAUUUGUGAAACUUAAAGCAAGUAUAAUGAAGAGAUACAUACUCAUUUUGUUUGUGUUCUGUUUCCAUUCCAUUAACUUCUACUAUCACUCAGGUUCAUCCUUGUUGAGGCCUAGACGAGUGGAAGGUUUCUCAUUUUGAAGUUAGUUGUUUUUUAAUUGGUCACGCAAAAGAAAGGCUUACAUUGAUUUUGAAAGACAAAACAUGUCAUUGUUUUUUUCACUAAUGCCCAACUUCUACAUGGCUGACUGGAUAUUGUUCAAAUUUUCCAAAAGAAUAGAAAAGAGAGAGAAACACCCUUCUUUUGGAUCCGAAGCCAGUCAUGGAAAAUUUCAUCCUGAAAGGAUAAUUUUUCAUAAAUAUGCAAGCAGCAGAAUGGCAGUGUGGCUGCAAUAGAAUCUGCCCCAGGACUUCCAUGCAUAGUACUUUGCUGUAAACACGAAACUACAGGCACACAUAUACUCAAAAGAAUACACAGUAUUGGAAGCCUAAUUAUUUCCACUAAGAUUGAGAUUAUUCCCUCUAAGAGCUAUACUGGAGAAAGCAAUGUGUCUUACUUCACUUUAUUCCACAUCAAUUCACAAAUUUUUAUAGCAUAUAUACUCUGUGAAAGGUGAUACUGGGCUAAAGAAAAUAAUUCUGCCCUCAGUUUGCAAUCUAACAGGGAAAAUAAAGUCCAUAUAUAUUAAAAUCUAAGUCUGUUUAUAAUAAGUGCCAAGUAGACAAUAUGGACAGGAAGUACUGUGGAUCUAAGGAGGUCAAGCUCAUGGGUGUACAGGUUGUAAUAGUUAUGAAGCCUUUUCAGUAGCAGUAGAACUUGAAUGAUGGGGUGGAUCGGGAUAAUGCACAGAGUGGGUGCAUGUGGAACACUUACAAGAAGAGGGGAUAUGGGGAGCUGAUGUCCACCAAGAACAGGGAGCCUGUAGUCUGCGGGUGUAUGUGGGGCCCUGCUGUAGUGGUGUUGAUUGACCUCUGUAGGCACUUUGCCUUCCUUCUUCUGUGUUCCCUCCAGCUAGGGUAGAGAGGACUGGUUCAGCUUGGCUCUUCCGGGCCUGCCCAAAGGACCAUGCAACAUGAAGGUGAAGUCCUUGUAGAGCAAAGGGCAUGAGAAGUCUCUCUUCUAAACCUAGGCUCUGCCCUGUCUCCAUAAUUUUAUUUCAUGAUGUUAGAUCUGGGAAGAGAUUUAGCACAUUUCUGUAUUAGUAGAGCAUUUGAGGGAGAUGAUAACUAUUAAACAAGAGAGGUAAAGAGAAACAUUCAGAGAUGAACAGGUUUAUUGGGAUAAAGAGUGAGGGUACAGAUUUGAGGCUACCAUUCACAGACCAGGGCUAGCUAUUCUAGAAACAAUAGAUGUCAUUAGACAAAUAAUGACAUGAUGGUUUGAUAUUGGUGUUCUAAACCUCCAGAGGUUAAUAACUUUGUUGGAUUUCAGUGGUGGACACCAGCAAUCUUAGGAGGUCUAGCAGCAAGACUGGUUCUUGCCAAGUUAGGAGAUGUUAGUUUGUUAGUGCUGAUUGGAUGGAAUAAGCAUACAACCGCUCUGUGUGCCCCCUUCUUUCCCCUCUGCAGGGUGUGAGAAUGGAAAAAGAGAAUUACACUUCUGAUAACCUAAAUAUUCGCUAACCUGUGGUGGGGAUGCUUAUUUUGGCCUUUUAGGCGCAAACUUGUUUCUUUAACUGUUAGUUUUAUGGUGCCCAGGGUUAAACUUUAAAGUUGGACUGUUUACAUGCUUGCGACAUGGUGAACCAAACGGGGAAAGUAAGAUAAAAACAGGCUUGAUAAAGGCCAGCCGACUUCUGCCAGUAGGCUAAAACUCACAGACUCUCAGAUAUAUACAUACAUAUAUGGCCAAGAUGUCUUGCUGUUAAAUGGUCUUUAAGAGAGCAGAAAAGCCUUUUUAACAAAUGCACCUAUUGUAGAGUCUUUCCAAUAGCCUAUACCUUUCAACUUGUGAAGAUAAAUAAGAACAUAUGGUUUGUCUCAACAUGCUUUUAACAAAAACCAGAUGAACACAUGUAAAACAAUUAGAGAGUUGUCUUAGGUACCCUGAAGUUCUUAUACAGGAUAUUUGCUCUUCAUUCAACGUUUAUUGACUACCUACUGUGUUCCAGGCCACCAGACCCUGUGUUAGAGGUUAGAGAUUUAAAACUCUAGUAACUUAUGUAUUAUAAUCUAUACAUGUCAUUUAAAGACAUAGCAUUUUUGGGCUGAGUGCGGUGGCGCACGCCUGUAAUCCCAGCACUUUGGGAGGCCGAGGUGGGUGGAUCAUGAGAUAAGGAGUUCAAGACCAGCCUGGCCAAGAUGCUAAAACCCCGUCUCUACUAAAAAUACAAAAAUUAGCUGGGUGUGGUAGCAUGCACCUGUAAUCCCAGUCACUCGGGAGGCUGAGGCAGGAGAAGCGCUUGAACCCAGGAGGCAGAGGUUGCAGUGAGCCGAGAUCACCCCACUGCACUCCAGCCUGGGAGACAGAGCAAGACUCUGUCUCAAAAAAAAAAAAAAAAAAAAAAAAAAAAAAGGCAUAGCAUUUUCUUAAUAUAAUAAGCCUCCUGGUGGGAAGUAAUUGUGAUUGAGUGUCUAGGGCAAUGUAGUUAUCCUAAAUUUUAACCAGGUGAUUUUAAAAUCACCAUUUGGAAAAUGGUCCCAUUAUAUCUAUUUGUAAACUGAGUCAUGAAAAAGUUGUCAGAGUACCCAGGUAGGCGUUUAUGAUGCACCUAAGUACAGGCCAGCCAAAAUUGUUUUGGUUUUGGUGCUUCCACCUGUGAUUAAUGUCCCACUUGACUCCUUGAGCUGUUUCAUCUGAAAUUAUAUUCCUGAAAUUCAUCUGGCUCUGCUGAUUAUCUCUACCUGGGCCUGUGGAUGAGAUCAGAGAGACCAGAGCUGGGGCUAUUUCUUGGUAAUGCAACUGCCAUUCCCCAUGCGUGGACACAAAUAGACAAUGCCUGUGGGAAUCCAAACCCCAAGGACUGUGAGAGGCAUGCAUGCCCUGUAUUAAAGCAGCAGCCUGGCUUGGUGCUCACUAAGUGCAUGGUCAGCAGUCACUACUCCUGUGACAUGUAUUGUCUGAGUCACUCAUUUGGCACUUAUUACAUCCUGUCUUGGGUUAUUAGUAACCUUUGCAUGCAUUUGUUUCUCCUCCCCAGCCACACCGCCCCAGUGGUGCAGACUCAGGGUUCUCCUCGCCAUUCAAAUUCUUCACCAGUGCUCUUUAUGGGCAGUAAACUUGGUUUUUAUUUUAAUUAUGAAAUGGUAGUGUUUAAGCUUAUUAAAAUAUAAGUGUUGUUUAUCCAAACAAUCAUAAAUGAACUUAUUAAAUUUUUUACAAACAGCUUUACUGAGACAUCUCUGACAUACAAACUGCCCAUAUUUAAAGUGUAGAAUUUGAUAAGUUUGAACUUCAUAAUAUGAUUUCUUAUUCUUUUUUUCAGAUAACAUGAUUUCUAACUCAUUUUUUACAGAUAACAUGAUUUCUUACUCAUUUUCUUUUUCAAAAUGAUGUUUGAUGAGCACCGAUUUUACAGAGGGUGCCUGUCUGAGAGUACGAGGUAGGAACUUUUGAAAUAACACACUGGUGGUAAGGGGGUAGUUUGGUUCCCAGAUAACUUUGAGAUUCUAGUUUUAUUUUUUAUUUAUUUAUUUUUUUUGAGACAGAAUCUUGCUCUGUUGACCAGGCUGGAGUGCAGUGGCACGAUCUUGGCUGACUCCAACCUCUGCCUCCUGGGUUCAAGUGACUCUUGGGCCUCAGCCUCCCAAGUAACUGGGAUUACAGGCACACAUCACCUUGCCUGGCUAAUUUUCUUUUUGAGAUGGAGUUUCACUCUUGUUGCCCAGGCUGGAGUGCAAUGGCGCGAUCUCCACUCACUGUAACCUCCACCUCCUGGAUUCAAGCAAUUCUCCUGCCUCAGCCUCACAAGUAGCUGGGAUUACAGGCAUGUGCCACCAUGCCUGGCUAUUUUUGGUAUUUUUAGUAGAAACGGGGUUUCAUCAUGUUUCAACUCCUGACCUCAGGUGAUUCACCCACCUCAGCCUCCCAAGGUGUUGAGAUUAUAGGUGUGAGCCGCCACGCCCAGCCAAGAUUCUAGUUUUCUGCCACGGUAAAUUGAGGUGUUCCUGGCAUAUAGUAGGCAAGAAAUAAAGCCUGUUUAUUGAAGGCUAUGUGUAUGUAGUUGUAAAGUCACCUCAGUUCUCUUUACGAAAAAAGAAUAUUGUACGUCUUUUAUUUAUUUUUAAUGGGGGAAUAGUUUGUAAUGGCCUUAGUAACUUUGAGCAUUUUAUCCUCUUGACAAAUCCAGCAGAGAUUUUACUUCCUGAAUGAAAGGAUACUGGCUAGCCAAGCGUUGGUUGAAAUGUUCAGUGGGGAAAGUAAGUUGAUAUUCCUAUCACCGCAGAAUCUCUUUGUCUCUGGAUUUCCCUUUGAUUUUCACAAGGACUGAGCAAGUCCUGCAGGUAAUUCAGUGCCAGGGCAGGCUAGCUGAGUUUUAAUUGAUGCUAAUUAGCACCCCCAUAGACUGUGACAAUUUUUUCCCCUCAAGCAGUCAGCCAAGUGGCAUUAGGAAAUGUGAGACAUCUUUCUUUGGAAUCGUCAUAGGAGCAGAACUAUUUUCAGGCCCAGUCUCCUUGGCAGGUCUUGCCCUUCUCAGAAAUAGUGAGGAAAUGAGAUAAGAAAAGUAAUACCCCGAGGAGUAAGGUGCCAAGUAGUUCUAGACCCAACUGUGGGCUUAGGACAGCAGGGAGAGGAUGCUGAAGGAUUUUGCUCUCAAGUACCUUUGCUUCUAGUUGGAAAGAAUGAGAGAUAGGAUGGAAUGAAGUCUGACUGCUGCAUGGGAGCUGGGGGGAAAUGCUUUGCGGGAGCAGUAUUUAUGGCAAGUUCAGAAGACAUCUUCUUACCUUGAACAAGUCAUUAGAGCUGGAACUGUAUACUGAUGACAAAAGAUAAAAUAUAACAAGAUAAACGGUCCCAGGCAGUCUUGUGUGCUCCGUCCUCCCAGCUAUACUCCACUGGAAUCCAGUGUCUGCCUUUGGUGGUAGAUGUUCCUGUUUCUCCAUCCCUUGGCUAGAUAUAUAUUAUCCAUUGAUAGGCAGCUAAGUUUGCAGCCAAUUCUCAAUCAUUUCUUGUGGUGGGGGACAGAAAUAAUGUGGGAAGCUAAGUUCACCAUCAACCCAGGGACUUAUUAGCUGGAAGUUUCAAACUGCCUUGCCACUGAACACCAUAAACAACUUCAGACCACAGCUGACUUGGUGUUUGCUGGUAGGAGGGAGUGAGAAAUUAUGCCAGAGGUGGGAAAACUUGUCAAGUCAAGGGGGAGGUCUCUUUAUUCUUCCCCUGUGCAUUCAGAGAGGUGAUGGUGUCUCUCUACCUCAUUGAAACCUGCUCCCAGGAGCUUCUGAAGUUGGCCAUUUAGAACCCAGUGUGAAUAUAAGGCAGUGGAUUCCCUUUUUCAGGAAAUUUGUAUUUUGAAUCUAGACCUCUUUGAUUAACCAGAAGGUCUUGGCUCCUGGUGAAGAAACCAUGAGGAGAUGGGGGGAUAGGCAAGCAUGAUUCUGAAAUGACGCUGGGGAGGAUCAGGGCUAUUUCAUCUGUGCUCACAUGAACACCACAGUCAAGCCUAAGGCUGGGCUUUCAGAUAUCUGACCUAGACUCUCUAUAGGAAAUAUAUUCUGCCUUGCGGCAUAGCAUGCACCAUAAGGAGCAGUGGAAUAGCACUUACCCUCACUACAUUGAGAGGCAUUUGAUCUAUGUUAAUAACCUAUUAUUUUACUUAAAAAAUGUUGGUUGGACCUACAAUAUUGAUUUUACAACCCCCUAGUGGCAUGUGACCUACAGGGCUAAGCUGAGUUGCUCUUUCUGGUUUCCUGCAUCUGGGCGCCUAGUCAGGGGGCAAGUUGGGACUGCACCUCGAUUUUCAUUUCUUUUGCCAAAUGGGCACCCAGACUUGGGGCUGGGUCUGCCAGAGGUGGCAGUGCUUUCUGUGACGUGUGUAAGGGGUAGUGUGCGCAUCCAAGGAGGGAAUGCAUGGGACUUGUGUGUCCCCAGUCAACCCCAUUUGUAAUUUGCAAAUAGGAUCUGUGUGGCUGGCAGGGGGCUGGCAGUGUGCACCAGAAAGAGGAAACAGAAGGUAGACUCCCAGGUGAGGAAGAGCUAGAUCCAGAGGGAGAAACGACACCCGCCCUGGCUUUGGCACUGGUUAGAAAGUCUGUUCCUGGCUUUUUCCUCAUGGCCCUUCUUUCACUUUGUGGUCUGAAAAUUGGCCAAAAGAUCAGGAAGGUGCUGAAUCAAGACGAGAAUAAAAGGGCACUUGAAACCUAAACACGGGCCAAUGACUCCUGGAUAACCAAAACCUGGCUGAAGGGAAGAGCUAACAUUCUAUCUGCAUGGAAAAGUAAAGGAAGAUCAGUUCUCUGAUGAAAAUGAGAAAUAUUAUUAUUAAGUUGAUCAAUACUUUGUUGAAAACUUUCUCUGUACCUGGUACUAAGAUACUCUGUUGUUUAAAUAGCUUCUUAUAGUCACUGUGGAUUACAGUAAUUUCUUUUUACAAGAUGUAAGAUUUGCCCAUCUGCAUAAAUACCCAUAUUUUAAUUCUAUGAUUUGUCUUUACUUCUAGCUACUCACUAAACAUACAUUUCCUGAAAGCAGAAGAGAUUCAAUUGCUGUUAUUCACAUGAUUACUAUCGUGCCAGGAGGGAGUGUCAGGGAAGUUAACAAAACAGGCCAGGUGUGGUGGCUCACAACUGUAAUCCCGGCACUUUGGGAGGCCGAGGUGGGCUGAUUGCUUGAGGUCAGCAGUUUGAGACAAGCCUGAGCAACAUGGUGAGACCCCAGCUCCAAAAAAAAAAAAUACAAAAAUUAGCCAGCCAUUGUGGUAUGUGCCCGUAGUCUCUUGACUGUAGGCAACUAGAAGUCUUUCCCCAGGUACGGGGGGCAGUGGUAUAGGACAGCUUUUAAGGGGGUAGAAUGUGACUCAGGCUUUCGUGGACUGGGUAGUAUUUGGAUAAGCCUGGUGACAGUCUGCACACUAUAGACUAGAGCACUCUGCUGUGACAGGUAUGCCUGAAUAGAACUCACGAAGAUCCUGCUCUGGCAAUUUAGUCACUGCCUAUCCACGGAUAGAACCCUGACUAUUCAGUAGUCACAAUAGACAAAUGAUAGCUUAGCAGAUUUUGGUUAUUAUUACUAUUUUAAAAUUUAAGUAUAGGAGAUUUUGCAUCAAUCAUAUAGAAUCACAUAUGGAAUUUCUUAGAAUGGGAUCUUAGUGCCUUAUCUUGUAUAUGUCCUGUAUAAAACGCACAGCUGAUCCUAUGAAGCCUGGCAAGUUUUAAAGGGAAGGAGUAUGCAAGCAGAAACCCAGAGGGCUUUAGCAGGGUAAAUGUAGAUGGAGAGGCCUAGAGAAAAACUUUUCCUUCUUUAUAAUUUUCCUGCUUCUAUUCUGUUUCACCUAAAUCCCAGAGCUGAAAUCAGCAAUUUAAUUGUCUUCCUUUCUCUUCUUCCGUAAGGGUUUGCAGAAUACAGAGCUAACAAGAUUACAUGGGGCUUAGGGGGUCAUGCUGCCAACAACAUAAGGAGGUCUACUACUACUGCCUUUAUUCACCAUUUUUCUGUGGGCACUAGCUGAUGCACUUGGACAAAAGAGAAAAAGACAGGGUGAAUGGAAAGCAGCCCUUUGACAGAAGAAAGACAGAGACCAGUUUCCAGUGAGCUCCUGAGGAUUGAUCUGGAGCCAGAAGGAAGAGUGUAUGUGAUCAUCGAUCUCUCAGGGUCGUCGGGUGAAGCCCCUAAAGACAAUGAAGAGCGUGUGUUCAGGGAACGCAUGCGGCCGAGGAAGCGGCAGGGGGCCGUCAGGCGCAGGGUCCAUCAGGUCAACGGCCACAAGUUCAUGGCCACCUAUCUUCGGCAGCCCACCUACUGCUCCCAUUGCAGAGACUUCAUCUGGGGUGUCAUAGGAAAGCAGGGAUACCAGUGUCAAGUCUGCACCUGCGUGGUCCACAAGCGGUGCCACGAGCUCAUAAUCACAAAGUGUGCUGGGUUAAAGAAGCAGGAGACCCCCGACCAGGUGGGCUCCCAGCGGUUCAGCGUCAACAUGCCCCACAAGUUCGGUAUCCACAACUACAAGGUCCCUACCUUCUGCGAUCACUGUGGGUCCCUGCUCUGGGGACUCUUGCGGCAGGGUUUGCAGUGUAAAGUCUGCAAAAUGAAUGUUCACCGUCGAUGUGAGACCAACGUGGCUCCCAACUGUGGAGUGGAUGCCAGAGGAAUCGCCAAAGUACUGGCCGACCUGGGCGUUACCCCAGACAAAAUCACCAACAGCGGCCAGAGAAGGAAAAAGCUCAUUGCUGGUGCCGAGUCCCCGCAGCCUGCUUCUGGAAGCUCACCAUCUGAGGAAGAUCGAUCCAAGUCAGCACCCACCUCCCCUUGUGACCAGGAAAUAAAAGAACUUGAGAACAACAUUCGGAAAGCCUUGUCAUUUGACAACCGAGGAGAGGAGCACCGGGCAGCAUCGUCUCCUGAUGGCCAGCUGAUGAGCCCCGGUGAGAAUGGCGAAGUCCGGCAAGGCCAGGCCAAGCGCCUGGGCCUGGAUGAGUUCAACUUCAUCAAGGUGUUGGGCAAAGGCAGCUUUGGCAAGGUCAUGUUGGCAGAACUCAAGGGCAAAGAUGAAGUAUAUGCUGUGAAGGUCUUAAAGAAGGACGUCAUCCUUCAGGAUGAUGACGUGGACUGCACAAUGACAGAGAAGAGGAUUUUGGCUCUGGCACGGAAACACCCGUACCUUACCCAACUCUACUGCUGCUUCCAGACCAAGGACCGCCUCUUUUUCGUCAUGGAAUAUGUAAAUGGUGGAGACCUCAUGUUUCAGAUUCAGCGCUCCCGAAAAUUCGACGAGCCUCGUUCACGGUUCUAUGCUGCAGAGGUCACAUCGGCCCUCAUGUUCCUCCACCAGCAUGGAGUCAUCUACAGGGAUUUGAAACUGGACAACAUCCUUCUGGAUGCAGAAGGUCACUGCAAGCUGGCUGACUUCGGGAUGUGCAAGGAAGGGAUUCUGAAUGGUGUGACGACCACCACGUUCUGUGGGACUCCUGACUACAUAGCUCCUGAGAUCCUGCAGGAGUUGGAGUAUGGCCCCUCCGUGGACUGGUGGGCCCUGGGGGUGCUGAUGUACGAGAUGAUGGCUGGACAGCCUCCCUUUGAGGCCGACAAUGAGGACGACCUAUUUGAGUCCAUCCUCCAUGACGACGUGCUGUACCCAGUCUGGCUCAGCAAGGAGGCUGUCAGCAUCUUGAAAGCUUUCAUGACGAAGAAUCCCCACAAGCGCCUGGGCUGUGUGGCAUCGCAGAAUGGCGAGGACGCCAUCAAGCAGCACCCAUUCUUCAAAGAGAUUGACUGGGUGCUCCUGGAGCAGAAGAAGAUCAAGCCACCCUUCAAACCACGCAUUAAAACCAAAAGAGACGUCAAUAAUUUUGACCAAGACUUUACCCGGGAAGAGCCGGUACUCACCCUUGUGGACGAAGCAAUUGUAAAGCAGAUCAACCAGGAGGAAUUCAAAGGUUUCUCCUACUUUGGUGAAGACCUGAUGCCCUGAGAGCCCACUGCAGUUGGACUUUGCCGAUGCUGCAAGAAGGGGUGCAGAGAAGACUCCUGUGUUGGAGACACUCAGCAGGUCUUGAACUACUUCUCCUCCUCGGAGCCCCAGUCCCAUGUCCACUGUCUAUUUAUUGCAUUCCCUUGCCCCAGGCCACCUCCUCCCCCUCCCACCUGGUGACCAGAAGGCGCUCUCGGUUCUUGUCUCACCAGUAAUGCAGACUCAUUGGGUCAGCAAUUAGCUGUAUACACUGCCGUGUUUGGACCAUUGGCAAGCCUGGUUCCACUCCUCAGGGGCUCCUGGCAGUGAAGCAACUUCAGUUCUUUUACUGCAAAGAACAGAAAAAAGAAAGAAAGCAAACAAGAAGACUCCGGCUCUGCUAUCGGACACAGAUCCUGAUCCCUCUUGCUUCUUUUCCCUCCUGCACCGCAGCUUGCCAUCCCUGCCCUUCUGUCCUGGAGAAGAGACUGGUGCUUCUCCGCACACACGAGGGAGGGCGCCCUUGAGGCAUGCCCUCUGAGGGAGGGAGACCAGAGAUGCAGGGAUUGGCCAGCUGGGUUGGUUUGCUCUGGAAUGGCUAACUCUUGCCUGCUUUGGUUUUAGCUUUUCAGCAUGCCAAAGUCAUGUAAGUUUGUGUCUUGUGGAAGAAAUCCUCUUUGUGGAAAAAGAAACAGGGUUUUGAACUCUGUUAACAUUUGAAAAAUAUAUUUUCAAAUUCACUUUCUAAUUGGCCAAAAGAGAUGAGUUCCAGUCUGAAUACAGGUAGAUAUUAAAGGGCUAAUAAAAAAUGAGAAACCGGUCGUCCAAGGUGGAUGCUGUCAAUGCCCGAGUGACACAUGAGAGCUGUAUGAAUUGAGAGAAAAGGCAACAAGUAGCAUUCUUCAUCAUUCAAGUUCUACCUGGACACAAAGGCGAGGACCCUGGGGUUCCAACAAAGCUCAGCUCCCAGAUUCUCUUUCCAGUUUCAUCCUAAGUUCCUAGCAUAAACACUAUUUAUUUUCUGCAGCAGUGUGUUAUUUUUGCGCACUUAUACAAAAUGGUAGUACUACUGUGUUGUGGUUUUUAAACAUUAAACAUGUAAAGUUAUAUACGAAAUAUCUGCUUUUGGAAUAAGCAGAAUGAGGCUAAACAUGGGUUAUACAAAGGGUAUCUGGAAACUGAAGAGCAACUUGUUAGAAAACUGACAAUGUCGCAAGAUGUACUCAGUUUUGUUUCUGUGUGACAUGCAAUGGCAACUCAUGUGGACACUAUUGAAGGGAUGUGACAUUACCUCCUGUAGAUAUGCUAACAGUGUUAUUCUUUCAUUUCCAAGGGUUCUCUGUGGCUUUGUGUAUAUGUUUCCCAGAGGUCAUUUGAUUACCUAAUUUACUGAACUGAUUUAGCAGGGAAUGGAAUCCAUUCCAACUAUUGCACGUGGAUUUCCCAGCUGCCCCUAAAUAUAUAUACUUGUGAGUGGCAAAGUGGCACUAAUGAAGCUUUUGCCUUUUGUACAUUUGAGAUUUUUGUAUAUAGUGUUUGCUGCAAGGCCUGUGGAAUUAAUUCGUUGCAUAUAGAGGUAUCAACUGCUGCAUGUUCAGGCAUAUUAUAAAACUUUAGUCUAUGAAAGAAUAAUUAUAAUAAUGUCCAGGUGCAAUACUCUGUAAGUCUAUUGGUUCAAGUUACCGAGAGAUAGGUGUGUUCCUUUAUGGGGGAUGGGGGGGUGUGUUGGGGAUUCUUUGUAUUGUUUAUUUCAUUUUGGUUUAUUUUAAAAGAUGUAAACAUAUAUUAAGCUAUAUUAAAUCUCACAUACAGUUCUUCUGUGCUCUAUUAUACCCUGAUAGAGAUGGGGGAGAGAAAGGAAUGUUUUUGAUGGUGGUUUCAAAGCUCGGACAGUAACUAUCUUGAGCCCAUUAGAGAGUCUGUGUCCAUAUUUGCAUCUGGCUGGUCAUAGCCUUUGUUACUAAUGAUGACAUUCAGUUCUCUUUUGUUUUUAUUUUUUAAAAACUCAGGUGUAAUUAUUAUCUGUUCUUAAGAUAAUUGCAAAUAUUAAAUAUUAUGAUAUAUCAAUUCAUGUGUUUGGCAUACCAGUGAAUGAUGAAGAACAUGAGAUUAAUUUAAUUUAUCUUCGGUAACUUGACAUUCUGGAGAGAGACUAUCUUCUGGAGUUGAGUACAAGCACAGAAACAUCUUUACGGUGGCAUCAUCUCAUUUUUUAGGAAGACAUGAUAAUACUGCCCAUCAUAUUCAUGUGUAACUACUGUUCUUUCUUCUGCUUUCUUCACCAUAAUAAACUUUGGACAACCAAGCAAGCUCUAACCGCAAUGCCAGAUGGCCUUGUCCGAGGGCCUAGUGUUUGCACGGCAGUGGGAACUGGGCCUUUCCUACAGGACAACUGGCAAGUUUGCUGGGAAGUCAAAUAAUACAUUCCACCUGGCAGCUGAAGGCAGCCAGUCAGUCUGUCCCAGAAAGGGCCCUUUUCAGCACCCAAAGCUGGGCUGGCUGGGAUGCCUCUGGCUGGUGAAGUUCUCACAUAGGCUGAUUUAAAUCCAGCAAAGGUCUAUAGAAAAAGGCUUGCGUGUUCGUUGAGUAAUCAUUGUUUCAUUUUCAUUUUUACGAGAGUUUGAAAAUAGACACACUGUUAACACUUCUGCCAGUUUUUUCUGAUCUUUCCAGCCCCACCCCCUUUCUCUUUCUCUCUCUCUCUCAAAGAAAAAAAAAAUGGGAGUGCAAAAAAAACAAAGCCAAAAAAUAUAUGAAGGAUAGCUGUUCUUCUGUGUUCUCUCAUUAUGGACUUUGUGAAGUAGAAACAUAAUUUUUUUUCCUCCAAAGGUGAAAAAACAAUGCAUUCUUGCUUUAAAAAAAAAAAAGAAGGCUAAAAAAUUACCUCUUUUUAAAUUAUGUGCAAAAUAAUUCUGGCUAACUGUAAAAUGUAUUCAAUUUUAGGAUUUUUUUUUUUUGUAUUGUGAUGCUUUAUUUGUACAUUUUUUUCCUUUCUGGAUGUAAUUUUAAUCUCUUGCCAUUCAUUAGUGUUAUUUCAUUGUAAACGUUAUUGUGCCAAAUGUACUGUAUUCAAAAGGAUGUGAAUGUGUAUUGUUUCAGAACCUAAUAAAUACAAUGACGUUAAGUCUUA